GCAAUGUCUCUUGACAGCGGCGGCGGCGCAGCCGGUUCCGGGUUCGGCGCGGGGCGGGGAUGUGAAUCCCGAUGGAGCGGCCCGAGGAAGGCAAGCAGUCGCCGCCGCCGCAGCCCUGGGGACGGCUCCUGCGUCUGGGCGCGGAGGAGGGCGAGCCGCACGUCCUCCUGAGGAAGCGGGAGUGGACCAUCGGGCGGAGACGAGGUUGCGACCUUUCCUUCCCCAGCAAUAAACUGGUCUCUGGAGAUCACUGUAGAAUUGUAGUGGAUGAAAAAUCAGGUCAGGUGACACUGGAAGAUACCAGCACCAGUGGAACAGUGAUUAACAAGCUGAAGGUUGUUAAGAAGCAGACAUGCCCUUUACAGACUGGGGAUGUCAUCUACUUGGUGUACAGGAAGAAUGAACCGGAACACAACGUGGCAUACCUCUAUGAAUCUUUAAGUGAAAAGCAAGGCAUGACACAAGAAUCCUUUGAUACCUCAGGUGCAGGUGCAGGGCGAGGGGCCGAUCCCCGGGUCCCUCCGUCGUCGCCCGCCACUCAGGUGUGCUUUGAGGAACCACAGCCAUCAACAUCGACGUCAGACCUCUUCCCCACAGCCUCGGCCUCUUCCACGGAGCCUUCUCCUGCAGGGCGAGAGCGUUCCUCCAGUUGUGGGUCUGGGGGUGGUGGCAUCUCCCCUAAAGGAAGUGGUCCCUCUGUGGCAAGUGAUGAAGUCUCCAGCUUUGCCUCAGCUCUCCCAGACAGAAAGACUGCGUCCUUUUCGUCGUUGGAACCCCAGGAUCAGGAGGAUUUGGAGCCCGUGAAGAAGAAAAUGAGAGGAGAUGGGGACCUUGACCUGAACGGGCAGUUGUUGGUCGCACAACCGCGUAGAAAUGCCCAAACCGUCCACGAGGACGUCAGAGCAGCGGCUGGGAAGCCAGACAAGAUGGAGGAGACGCUGACAUGCAUCAUCUGCCAGGACCUGCUGCACGACUGCGUGAGUUUGCAGCCCUGCAUGCACACGUUCUGCGCGGCUUGCUACUCGGGCUGGAUGGAGCGCUCGUCCCUGUGUCCUACCUGCCGCUGUCCCGUGGAGCGGAUCUGUAAAAACCACAUCCUCAACAACCUCGUGGAAGCAUACCUCAUCCAGCAUCCAGACAAGAGUCGCAGUGAAGAAGAUGUGCAAAGUAUGGAUGCCAGAAAUAAAAUCACUCAAGACAUGCUGCAGCCCAAAGUCAGGCGGUCUUUUUCUGAUGAAGAAGGGAGUUCAGAGGACCUGCUGGAGCUGUCAGACGUUGACAGUGAGUCCUCAGACAUUAGCCAGCCAUACGUCGUGUGCCGGCAGUGUCCUGAGUACAGAAGGCAGGCGGCGCAGCCUCCCCACUGCCCAGCACCCGAGGGCGAGCCAGGAGCCCCACAGGCCCUGGGGGAUGCACCCUCCACGUCCGUCAGCCUGACGACAGCAGUCCAGGAUUACGUGUGCCCUCUGCAAGGAAGCCACGCCCUGUGCACCUGCUGCUUCCAGCCCAUGCCCGACCGGAGAGCGGAGCGCGAGCAGGACCCGCGUGUCGCCCCUCAGCAGUGUGCGGUCUGCCUGCAGCCUUUCUGCCACCUGUACUGGGGCUGCACCCGGACCGGCUGCUACGGCUGCCUGGCCCCGUUUUGUGAGCUCAACCUGGGUGACAAGUGUCUGGACGGCGUGCUGAACAACAACAGCUACGAGUCAGACAUCCUGAAGAAUUACCUGGCAACCAGAGGUUUGACAUGGAAAAACAUGUUGACCGAGAGCCUCGUGGCUCUCCAGCGGGGAGUGUUUCUGCUGUCUGAUUACAGAGUCACGGGAGACACCGUUCUGUGUUACUGCUGUGGCCUGCGCAGCUUCCGUGAGCUGACCUAUCAGUAUCGGCAGAACAUUCCUGCUUCCGAGUUGCCAGUGGCCGUAACAUCCCGUCCUGACUGCUACUGGGGCCGUAACUGCCGCACUCAGGUGAAAGCUCACCACGCCAUGAAAUUCAAUCAUAUCUGUGAACAGACAAGGUUCAAAAACUAAGCAUCCAGAGGCCCUGAGCAGCUUUCAGCACUGGAGGUGAAGAGAGCGUGUUUUUAAAAUACAGAGACAAGCACGUCAAGGUGUUUUCACAGCCCCCUGAGGGAAGGGACGCAGGGUCUCCGACAGGUGCUCUGGGGUGACUCUUCUGUGGAGCUUUACCCUCUGAGUGAGACCCUCCCCAGAGCCCCGGGGGCCGCAGCCCGCCCUCCUGGUGAGCGCUGGGCAGGGCUCGUGGUGGCAUCAGCAGCAGAGACGAAGCCUUUCUGUAACAUGCGGCCGUCCCGCCGAGAGGGGCAGUUUUGCUCUUUUGUACAUUUUCCGAAACUACAGUUAAAGCAGAAGUCUGUUUUUAGGAAAAGUUUCAAGGGAGAAGGGCAAGUUUAUCAAAAACAUUGUUUCAGGAGAAGGGAGCAUAAGUUUACAGCCUACAGGACGUACACAAUAUCCUGCUGCUGGGAAAACCACAGCAUUUUAUCUAUUUUUUAUUUUAAUAGGUUUGGUGCUUAUCUUCUAAUAAGAUUUAAAUGUCACAAACUGUAGCACAAAUAAUAUAAUUUAUAAUUUACAAAUUGACUAAAAUUGGGUAUAGUAUGGUAUUUGAAAGAAUAAGCAUAUGCUUCUGUUUAUUAAAAAAAGAAACCUUCCAAUGUCCAAAACUGCUAACCCUCGACGUGGCCGCCAAGUUAGUCGCUCCUUGCUAACCGGUGAGUGACCGCGGCCCCGAGCCUGGGGCUGGACGCAGGUCCCAGGACAUGCUGCUCCCUUGUGUGAGUGACCGCGGCCCCGAGCCUGGGGCUGGACGCAGGUCCCAGGACGUGCUGCUCCCUUGUGUGAGUGACCACGGCCCCAAGCCCAGGGCUGGAGGCAGGUCCCAGGACGCGCCGCUCCCUCAUGCUGCCCGGGCCCUUCCUCCAAGACCCUACAGAGCCUGAGGGGCACCUUGGCUUCCGCCUGUGCUAGCUUUGCCAUGUCAUCUGGAAUAAUACUUGAAAUUUUGAUUUUUGGAAAAAAAAGUUUUUUAUCUUUUGUUGAAAUCACCUGUUAUCCUUGUUUGUAAACUGAUAACUUUUUUGCUUCUUCUCAGGAAUACAGUUUUCAACUGUUGUCUUGCUCUUGAUAGAAACUGAGAAGCAGCAAUCUGUAUUUGUGGAGGAAAGUCCUCUCUUUUGCAUAUUCUAAUAAAUGAGCCGCGUUUGCUCCUCCGCUCUCGUGUUGGGCUCGUGUCUGGGGCUGCCUCACUUCCCCAUGCGAGGGAGGCAGGCCCCAUGCAGAGUGAGCUCCGAGUGCCUCACUGCUAGUGAUGGUCACUCUGUCACCUGCUGUCCCUCAGUGACUCCUGUGAAACCUGCUCAGGUCUCUUCAUUCUGCCAAUGCUGGGAAGCCACAACCUGUUCAUCCAGUGUGGAGGCUUUGUCUUCAGCUGAGCACCAGAAGAAGCCACAAUGCAGAGACCCUGAGUUUGUGCAAGGGUGGGGCUGAGAGGGGAGGUCCCGUGUUAGUGCAGGGGUGAGGCCGGGAGGGGAGGUCCCGAGUUUGUGUAGGGGCGAGGCUGAGCAGGGAGGUUCUGAGUUAGUGCAGGGGCGAGGCUGAGCAGGGAGGUCCCGAGUUAGUGCAGGGGCGAGGCUAAGGGGGAGGUCCCAAGUUUGUGCAGGGGUGAGGCUGAGCAGGGAGGUCCCAAGUUAGUGCAGGGGCGAGGCUGAGAGGGGAGAUCCCGAGUUUGUGCAGGGGCGAGGCUGAGAGGGGAGGUCCCUAGUUAGUGCAGGGGUGAGGCCGAGAAGGGAGGUCCCAAGUUUGUGCAUGGAUGAAGCCAAAAGGGGAGUUUGCACGUUUGUGCAGGGGUGAGGCCAAGAAGGGAAGUCUUGAGUUGGUGCAGGGGUGAGGGAGAGGGGAGGUCCUGAGUUUGUGCAGAGGCGAGGCUGAGAGGGGAGGUCCCUAAGUGCAGGGGUGAGGCCGAGAGGGGAGGUUGCAAAUUUGUGCAGGGGUGAGGCCAAGAGGGGAGGUCCUGAGUUAGUGCGGGGGUGAGGCCGAGAGGGGAGGUCCUGAGUUUGUGCAGAGGCGAGGCUGAGAGGGGAGGUCCUUAGUGCAGGGGUGAGGCUGAGAGGGGGAGGUCCCAAGUUUGUGCAGGGGUGAGGCCGAGGGGAGGUUGCAAGUUUGUGCAGGGGUGAGGCCAAGAGGGGAGGUCCUGAGUUAGUGCGGGGGUGAGGCCGAGAGGGGAGUUCCUGAGUUUGUGCAGAGGCGAGGCUGAGAGGGGAGGUUGCCAGUUUGUGCAGGUGCGAGGCUGAGAGGGGAGGCUGGCAUUCGCCAAUGAAGUGGGCUGGGGCUACCCUGCGUCUGUGUCUUAGAGAGAUCGGUUGAUACUCACUCUUCCCCUUCCCAUCUCCAAAAAGUAGAAACAAGAACACUUGCCCUGUAGAGGAUGCUGGUCUUUCCUCAGGACCAGCUGCACCUGUCCAGGAAGGGCAGGCAGCUCAGAGAGCCUCUGGGCUCCAGGUGUCCUAGGGACUCACUCCUGCUUCCUUAGUCCUUCAGAGAAGUCCAACUCCUGGCCCACUGUGAAGAGGAUUUCUACCUGGAGCAGUCGGAACAGCUUGGGUUUGGCUGUGAUGUGAGGGAGGAGGCCUUGGGAGCAGGGCAGUUAUCCUCCCAGCGUGGUAAGGAGCCGUGUUUUAUGGAGGCAGGGAGAUCAGGGCAGUUACUCCUCGGGUGUGGUAAGGAGCUGUGUUUUAUGGAAGCAGGUGGCCGUGAACUCAUUCCGUCUUUUCAUGAGCUUCUGUACUUCCUCGUCCUCAAGACCCAGCCAUCCCACCCAGCAAAACUGACCGGCUGUGGUGGUUUUGGAGCCCUGCUCUCCUUGUGGGGUGGCUGCGUGGGUCGUCCACAGGCUUUCUGGAGGACAGCCUGGUGCUGCUGCAGAUCCCACUGCUUCUUCCUGGCUCCUUGGCCCAGCCUUGGGACAAACCCAGGGCAGGGCUGCAGCUGCCCGCUGGCCCCACAGACCGUCUCCCCACGCACUCCUCAUCUGCGGCUCCCUCUGUGCUCCCUGGUGCCCCUCAGAAGCGGGGGUCAGCCCUGCCCACCCCUCCGUGUGCUGCCCAGGCUCCAAGCCAGGGAAGGGGGCCUCAGGUUCUAGGUGAACCCGUCCACCCCAGUGAGGCCUCUCUGGGAUGGCCUCUGUCAUAGCUUCUGACUGCAGCCAGGAAGUCUGGGCAGAUUGGCUUAAAACAGACUGAGGGAUUCAGGCCAACCCUCCUCCCUAGGCCAGCUACAAAGGCUGUUUUAAAUCUGCUUUAAGUCAUCUUAAUGACCUCAGGGCCAGCAGGAUGGGAGUGGUCGGGCCCAGGUGUGAGAGCCGGGGUCCAGGGGCUGCUCCCAGCACCACACGGCCUUCACCCCAGGGGUGUGGCCAAGGCAGAGAGGCAGCUGAGUUUGGAAGGGGCUUCCGCCAGCAAGGGUUUCCUGGUGACAGCCCCCCAGCUUCGGGCUGGCAGGCUGGGAGAGUGGAGCAAUGCUGGCCCUGAGGCAGCUGCAGCCGGCUCCCUGAAGAGGCCCCAGAGUCACUGCCAGGGCCGCUAGGUUGCCGGGAGCCCUGCACUGGGAAGGGAAGGAAAGCAUGAGAACGGAGGGGAUUUAGGAAAGUAGAUCGUCCCUCCAGCCUGGCUUGAUGGGGAAACCAGAACGCUGUCCCCGCGGCCGUGCCCGCCCUCUGCCUCCACGUGGGCUCCGUUUUGGCAUGCACGCUAGCUCCUGCGCCUUCUGAGGGCGGCUGCAGCCGUGUAGAGAAGCCGGGUCUUGCCUCCCUGAGGACGGAGGGCCGCAUGCAGAGCACAGCCUAGCCCUGCAGAUCCGCGCGCUGACCAGCAGCAGGACGGAGCCGGGUGAUCUUCGGGGGAGCCACCUCCAGAAACGCCUAGUGCUGGUAACUGGUAGACAGCCAUUAUUCAAGCAUCCUCUACACUUAGAAUUGAGUUACACUGAAAACAAAGGUGAUGAGUGCUCAGGACGCACUACUUUCUAGUUAGUUUACCGCACCUGCCUGUUACCUGCAGGCCCGAGGGUGUGUGCUUCUGUGGCCUGUGUGGGAUGGCACCCCUUCCAGCCUUACCCACUCAGCUCAGUUGGCCUGGUUGGAAUGGGCCCUGGGAGGAGUGUUUGCACUGUGGAAAUUGGUAAAUGCUUCAAAUCAGGGUGGUUUUUAAUUUUGCUUUUGUUUUCUUCUGAAGAGAAGGUUGUUAAACACCAGCACAGUGCUGCACCAGGCAGCCAGCAUAUAAUCAUGAGAAAUAAGUAGUUGUUUAAGCCACUGCAUUUGGGGUGGUUUAUUACAUAGUAAUGAUAACCAUAUCAUGGCCCUUGAAGGCCCAGCAUGUAUGACCCCUGCCUCCACCCCUCAGAAAACCUCUUCUCCCUACCUGCUUCUCCUGGAGCCCCUCAGGUGUUCCUCUGCUUCUCCACCGAACCAGCUAAUUCUCACAAACAGCCCCUCAGGUACCAGCCCCUCCCUCUGCAGCCUCUCCUCAUUCAGCUCCUGCAGGGCUGCCCCCACCCCGCCAGCCAGUCUAGUUUCCCCCCAGCACCUGUCACUAUCGGAAAGGAAACAUCUGUUUACCGUUUGUCUCCCCCUCUCAAAAAAAUAGAGCAGGGAUCUUGCCUGUCUGCCCACUGUUGUUUAUUUGUCUGAAAUGUUUGGCCCCAGGGCAGCAUCUACUGAUCACUGACCAGUUGGCUACUGAACGGUGAAGGUCUGAUGAGCUGAUGAGCCGUCCCCUGGGCUUGAAAUCUUUCCCGCGGCACAAACAGGCGCCCCUUCCUCUGUCGCUCACUUUUCACGGUUGUCUCCUUCUGAGGCGGUGAGUCUAGAUGGUGGGGUCUUAAAGUUCCUCACACAGAGCAGACACUUGGUCGUGCAUGUCUGUGGAAGGAAUGGACUCAGGAGAGAAUGUUGAAGGCCAGUCAGACCAGGAGUGAGUGCCGUGCGCCGUGCUGGGAGCCUGUCACUGUGAGUGCCGUGCGCCGUGCUGGGAGCCUGUCACUGUGAGUGCCGUGCGCCGUGCUGGGAGCCUGUCACUGUGAGUGCCGUGCGCCCUGCUGGGAGCCUGUCACUGUGAGUGCCGUGCGCCGUGCUGGGAGCCUGUCACUGUGAGGGCCGAGCGCCGUGCUGGGAGCCUGUCACUGUGAGGGCCGUGCGCCGUGCUGGGAGCCUGUCACUGUGAGGGCCGUGCGCCGUGCUGGGAGCCUGUCACUGUGAGGGCCGUGCGCCGUGCUGGGAGCCUGGCACUGUGAGUGCCGUGCGCCGUGCUGGGAGCCUGGCACUGUGAGGGCCGUGCGCCGUGCUGGGAGCCUGGCACUGUGAGUGCCGUGCGCCGUGCUGGGAGCCUGUCACUGUGAGUGCCGUGCGCCGUGCUGGGAGCCUGUCACUGUGAGUGCCGUGCGCCGUGCUGGGAGCCUGGCACUGUGAGUGCCGUGCGCCGUGCUGGGAGCCUGGCACUGUGAGUGCCGUGCGCCGUGCUGGGAGCCUGGCACUGUGAGUGCCGUGCGCCGUGCUGGGAGCCUGGCACUCUGAGUGCCGUGCGCCGUGCUGGGAGCCUGUCACUGUGAGUGCCGUGCGCCGUGCUGGGAGCCUGUCACUGUGAGUGCCGUGCGCCGUGCUGGGAGCCUGGCACUGUGAGUGCCGUGCGCCGUGCUGGGAGCCUAUCACUGUGAGGGCCGUGCGCUGUGCUGGGAGCCUGGCACUGUGAGGGCCGUGCGCUGUGCUGGGAGCAUGCAUUUGUGAGACCCGCCCUGCCCAGUGCUGGCCUUGAAUGUGGGUCCACUUGGGCCGCUGGAUCAAAACGCCGCAGAACAGGCGGCUUAAACAACAGAAAGUAUUUUCUCACAGUUCUGGGGCCUGGAACUCUGAGAUCAGGGUGUCAGCGGGGCCGGUUCCUCUUUGGUCUGUCUCCUUGGCUCGUGGGCAGCAUCUCCUUGAGUUCUCACGUCAUCUUCUCUUCAUGCGUGUUUGUGCCCUAAUCUCUUCCUGCGAGGACACCAGUCCUAUUGGAUUAGGGCCCACACCAGUGGCCUCAUUUUAUCUUAAUCACCUCUUUAAAGACCACACCUACUAAAACUGGAACGAUAUAGAGAAGAUUAGCAUGGCCCACGUGCAGGCAUGACACCCAAAUUCAUGACGUGUUCCAUGUCUGCAGAUACAGUCACCUCUGAGGUCCUGGGAUUUAGGGCUUGAACAUAUUGUAACACUCUGCCAUCAAAGCUCGCACGCCACGGGGUUUUAUAAAAAUUGGGUGGUUUUGUUUGUUGUUGUUUGGCAAACCCCACAUGCUGGAUACCAUUGACACUCCGUGGUGGGCUGAGCCAUGUCCCCGUCCCGCCACCACAGAUACCCGUAUCCGAUCACUUGAGCCUGUGAUGAUGUUGCCUUGCACCGUAAAAGGGGCUUUGCAGAUAUGGUGGAAUUAAGGACCUUGAGAUGAGGGGAGGAUCCUGGAUUAGCUUGUGGGCCCUCUGUGCAACAGUAGGAGUCGUUGUAAGAGGGAAGCAAGAGGCCGGGCGUGGUGGCUCACGCCUGUACUCCCAGCACUUUGGGAGGCUGAGGCGGGCGGAUCACGAGGUCAGGAGAUCGAGACCAUCCUGGCUAACAUGGUGAAACCCCGUCUCUACUAAAAAAUACCAAAAAAUUAGCCGGGCGUGGUGGUGGGUGCCUGUAGUCCCAGCUACUCGGGAGGCUGAGGCAGGAGAAUGGCUUGAACCCGGGAGGCGGAGCUUGCAGUGAACCGAGAUCGCACCACUGCACUCCCGCCUGGGCGACAGAGCGAGACUCUAUCUCAAAAAAAAAAAAAAAAAAAAAGCAAGCAAGAAGUCAAAGGCAGGAAGAGGAGGCUUGGUGACAGAGAAGAGGUGGGAGGGAUGUGCUUUGCAGAGGGAGCAAGGGCCUCCAGCCAGGAGAGGAGGGCAGGCUGUCGAAGCAGAAAAGAAAACAGAUCUCCCUGCAGGGCCACCAGAAGGAACCAGCCCUGCCUGCCCCUUCAUUUUGGACUUCCGAGCUCCAGAACUGCAAGAGAAUAAAUCUAGUUUAAGCAGCAAAGUUGGUGGUAACUUCUUAGAGCAGCCACAGGAAGCUCACUACCCCCCACACACUCAUCCCGUUUGGUUUUUGUUUUCAGGAAGGGUCCAGUCUGUCUCAGAGGUGCUGUGGUUGGAGGUGGAGUGUGGGGCAUGGCUGAGCACCCAACAUCCGCUUCACCCUCUCCCCUGCUCCCCAGCACGUUCCUUCACCCUGUAGCUCUAGGUCUCUGUGGCAGACACUCAGCUCUAACUGCUGACCUGAUGGCUCCACUUGGUGUUCAAACAUCCCAGAUUCAUGUUGUCAAAGAGAGCUGUUUCCAGUGGGGACCCCAGGCCCACCACGUACGCCCGGCAGACCUGCCCUCUCCACUGUCAGAAGAUGGCAUGGCCUCCCUGUAGCUCAGGCCCAACCCCAGGAGUCAUCCUGCUGGCUGUCCUCAGUGCCCCAGGCUUCUCUUCAGGGGCUUCUUGUGGCUCUGAUUGUUGCCCCCUCACCUCACUGCUCUUCUCCCAGAUCUGUGCGUGCAUUGGUCCUCCUUGUCACGCACGUUCAGCUCAAAUAUUACUUCCUCAAAGGUGCCUUUGAGUACUCGUUCUCCUUGCCUUUCCCUCUCCUGGGACACUGUUCCCACCAGUACCUGCAUGAUUCCUUUUUUUUCUUUUCCUUUUCUUUUUUUGUUUUUGAGACAGUGUCUUGCUCUGUUGUCAGGGCUGGAGGGCAGUGGCGCAAUGUCAGCUCACUGCAGCCUCCACCUCCUGGGCUCAGAUGAUCCUCCCACCUCAGCCUCCUGAGUAGCUGGGACUACAGGUGCACACCACCACACCCAGCUAAUUUUUAGUAGAGAGCAGGGUUUCACCAUGUUGCCCAGGCUGGUCUUGAACUCCUGAGUUCAAGCGAUCUGCCCGCCUCUACCUCCCACAGUGCUGGGAUUCCAGGCGUAAGCCGCCACGCCCAGCAACUCCGUUUCUUACUUGUUGGCUCACAUUCUCCUGAGAAGUCCUCCCUCAACCAUCGGCCUGAAAUAGCAGCGAGCCUCCCCAGGGUUGCCUCUGCCUUUUCUUGACUCUUUCUGUCACCUUCUAUGCUUGUUGUCUGGUCCCCACUAGAAUAUACCUUCUGUAAGAGCAGGGAUUUGGGACAGUGCCUAGAAUAGUACUUGCAGACAGUAGGCUACGAUAAAUAUGAAUGACGGCCCCAUGCAGAUGGUAGCCCCUCUCGCUCGAACGCUUCACCCAGUUUUAUUUUCUUUUCAUCAGUUACCGCCCUCUGAAGGUAUCCACACACAAACAUGAAACUGGACCAAAGCAGGGACCCCCCGCACGCAGAAUAGUGCUGGGCUCGCGUAAGGCACCUCAGUGGGUCCAUCAGCUGAUGCAUGGACAGACAAAAUGGGUGUAUCCAGACACUGGAGUAUCGUGCAGCGAGGAAACGUGCUGAGUGUGGAUGGACCUUAAACACACCAUGCAAGUGAAAAGGCGUCACAGAAGGCCACAUACGAUAUGAUCCCAUUUCUAUGAAAUGUCCAGAAGAGGCACAUUCAUAAAGACAGAAGGUGACUGAGUGGUUGUCGGGCUGGGUGGAGGGGAUAGGGAGUGAAUGCAAGAAGGAUCCUUCUGAGGUAACGGAAGUAUCCGGAAACUGGGUUGGAGUGAUGGGUGCACAGCUCUGCACAUUUACUACAGUCGCUGAACUGCACACACAACACGGGUAUAUUUUAUUGCAUAGAAAUUGUAUUAAAGCUGUUAAGAAUUUUACUUAGAUUAGCAUUUUUCCCACACUGUGCCAUCAACUUAGUAUAUGAUUAGAUUCAUUGUUUCUAACUGUAUUUAAAUUUAAUGUUUGUCACAUUUUGCUUGCUAAAUUUUUAAAAUUUUAAAUUACUGUGGGUACAUAAAAGGUGUAUAUAUUUAUGGAGUACCUUGAUAUUUUAAUACAGACAUACAAUGUAUAAUGAUCAACUCCCAGUAACUGGGGUAUCCAUCACCUCAAGCCUGUAUCAUUUCUUUGUUAGGAACAUUCCAGUUCCACUCUUUUUGUUAUUUAAAAAUAUACAAUACAUUAUUAUUAACUAUAUUCACCCUCCUGUGCUAUGGAAUACUAGAUCUUAUGCUAAUUAAAUGUUUUCCCUAUUUCUCCCA